AUGCUUUUUCUGGAGUCCUGUAGAGAAAGUGCUCUCUGCCGCAUUGAUAGCAGCGAGAGCUGGAGGUGUUGGGUCGGGAGACCAGCCGUUCGAUCCCGCCGCAGGUAGGAGCUGGUUUCCAUCCUGGCACCACGGCACACACCUCCAGCCUCGAGCCCGGCGCUGCUGCCCGGGGGUCUCCUUCAGGCUCUUUGACGCCGUUCCAGGGGGCACCUAUCCAGGCAUCCUCUGGGCCUCUAGCCAGAGGACUGGCUCCCGGCUUCAGCACUCCGGGCUGCAGUAAGAAGUGCCCUUAUCGCUCUGAGCCCUGCCACCAUCCCGUGAACCACCGAAACCCUGGUCCAGCGCGACAGCCUUGGACCUGGGACUGGACGGAUCCAAAACGCUCAGCCUCGGCCCCCCACAGACGGGGCUCUGCAUCGUCUCUGAUAUGUCACCCACCAUCUCCCACAAGGACAGCAGCCGGCAACGGCGGCCAGGGAAUUUCAGUCACUCUCUGGAUAUGAAGAGCGGUCCCCUGCCGCCAGGCGGUUGGGAUGACAGUCAUUUGGACUCAGCGGGCCGGGAAGGGGACAGAGAAGCUCUUCUGGGGGAUACCGGCACUGGCGACUUCUUAAAAGCCCCACAGAGCUUCCGGGCCGAACUAAGCAGCAUUUUGCUACUACUCUUUCUUUACGUGCUUCAGGGUAUUCCCCUGGGCUUGGCGGGAAGCAUCCCACUCAUUUUGCAAAGCAAAAAUGUUAGCUAUACAGACCAAGCUUUCUUCAGUUUUGUCUUUUGGCCCUUCAGUCUCAAAUUACUCUGGGCCCCGUUGGUUGAUGCGGUCUACGUUAAGAACUUCGGUCGUCGCAAAUCUUGGCUUGUCCCGACACAGUAUAUACUAGGACUCUUCAUGAUCUAUUUAUCCACUCAGGUGGACCGUUUGCUUGGGAAUACCGAUGACAGAACACCCGACGUGAUUGCUCUCACUGUGGCGUUCUUUUUGUUUGAAUUCUUGGCCGCCACUCAGGACAUUGCCGUCGAUGGUUGGGCGUUAACUAUGUUAUCCAGGGAAAAUGUGGGUUAUGCUUCUACUUGCAAUUCGGUGGGCCAAACAGCGGGUUACUUUUUGGGCAAUGUUUUGUUUUUGGCCCUUGAAUCUGCCGACUUUUGUAACAAAUAUUUGCGGUUUCAGCCUCAACCCAGAGGAAUCGUUACUCUUUCAGGUAGUGUAUUUAAGCUAUUAUGGUGUUAGGUUUAUUUAUCCUUUUGAAAGAGUGUGUGACGUUGGAGGGAAGCUCAUUAAUUUACUGGAAAUCAUUGUAUGGGAGAUAACUCAAGAUUUCCUUUUUUUCUGGGGAACUGUAUUUUUAAUAACAACAACAUUGGUUGCCCUUCUGAAAAAAGAAAACGAAGUAUCAGUAGUAAAAGAAGAAACACAAGGGAUCACAGAUACUUACAAGCUGCUUUUUGCAAUUAUAAAAAUGCCAGCAGUUCUGACAUUUUGCCUUCUGAUUCUAACUGCAAAGAUUGGUUUUUCAGCAGCAGAUGCUGUAACAGGACUGAAAUUGGUAGAAGAGGGAGUACCCAAAGAACAUUUAGCCUUAUUGGCAGUUCCAAUGGUUCCUUUGCAGAUAAUACUGCCUCUGAUUAUCAGCAAAUACACUGCAGGUCCCCAGCCAUUAAACACAUUUUACAAAGCCAUGCCCUACAGAUUAUUGCUUGGGUUAGAAUAUGCCCUACUGGUUUGGUGGACUCCUAAAGUAGAACAUCAAGGGGGAUUCCCUAUAUAUUACUAUAUCGUAGUCCUGCUGAGUUAUGCUUUACAUCAGGUUACAGUGUACAGCAUGUAUGUUUCUAUAAUGGCUUUCAAUGCAAAGGUUAGUGAUCCACUUAUUGGAGGAACAUACAUGACCCUUUUAAAUACCGUGUCCAAUCUGGGAGGAAACUGGCCUUCUACAGUAGCUCUUUGGCUUGUAGAUCCCCUCACAGUAAAAGAGUGUGUAGGAGCAUCAAACCAGAAUUGUCGAACACCUGAUGCUGUUGAGCUUUGCAAAAAACUGGGUGGCUCAUGUGUUACAGCCCUGGAUGGUUAUUAUGUGGAGUCCAUUAUUUGUGUUUUCAUUGGAUUUGGUUGGUGGUUCUUUCUUGGUCCAAAAUUUAAAAAGUUACAGGAUGAAGGAUCAUCUUCGUGGAAAUGCAAAAGGAACAAUUAAUAUAUAUGCUACUGGACAUUCUAGCAAGGUAAUUGUAGUUUAGUUUUAAUUCGGAGAGCAAUGAUAAUCAGUGCACAGGAGUAUAAAAUAUUAUUUUAAACAGCGAAAUUAAUAAUAUAAAAUGCCAAAUGGUUGAAAAAAUAGAAACCUUUCUGUAUAUUUGAUCAUAUUUUUUUUUUGCCUUGUCAAUGUAUUUAAAGUUUACUUAAGGUCAGGAAAUUCUAAAACAACUUUUCUGGCCUUGUUAUUUGAUGUAUAUCUUUUAAAUUUACUGACCAAAGCAUGUUUUAAGCUGCAAUGCAGUAGUCACGGGUGGUAACCAUGUAGUCAGGUAUUGUUAUUAGUACCUAUCACUGCUGAGCUGUAUUUAAAAUUUUGGUACAAUAUAUAAAAUGGAGAAGAGCUUGAUAUUCAGGUACUAACCACAACUAGUCUGACAUUGUUGGCAGUUAAAAUCUUAUUUUGAAUUGUAAAUUAGUUAAAUUUUAUGUGGAAUUUGCUGAGAAAAGAAUAUAGACUACUGAAAUGUCAUUUUAGUUAUUUUUCUUAUGACCACAUUGUACAAAUGAAUCUGUGUUAAAAAGACUAUUUUAAAUGUAUUUCCUGCUUUUGUAAGCAUUAAAGAUUUAUAAGAAAAUUAUUCAAACUAUUUUUUAUAAAAUGAAAGUUAUGAUUUUUAAACUUAUUGAUUCCUCUUGCCCCUACCCCCUCUUUUUGGAAGAUAUUUUGAUUCCUUAUAAACUUUUACCCUAAGCUUAUAUAUGUUUUCUGUCACAAGUGCUUCCUGGCACACAGACAGCCAAUGGAGGGGAUCAAAUUCAGUGUUGUAUGUAUGUUUAUGGCAACAUUUUGAAAAUAAAAAUUAAAUGUUUUUCUUCAAGUAGUUUUUUUUUAAUUGCUGAGAGAAAAAAACAGUAAAGCUUUCUGAUUAAGUAAAAUUUAAAUGGGCAGUACCAUAAUUUAAAAAACUAAUACUUUAAAGAGAGAGACAAAGAUAUUUUGUGCCUUUGACAAAUUAAAUCUAAUAGUGGAAAAAUGUUUCUUAAUUAAGCACUUUACUAGUGAAAAAGAUCUCACAAUUUAUGCCAAAUCAGGUACUGUAUUUUCAUGUAUUAACACAUAACCUUUUGUUUGAAUACUAUAGUUUUCAGUGGACAGUUGCUAUUCCAAGAAAAUUAAGCUUUUGAGUACUUUAGCAAUUCCCAGCGUAUUACAUACACCCAGUGAUAAGGUUCUUUGCAUGUUUUGUGUUAUGUAUUACUCUGACUCUUUAGAGAUUAUAUAAAUCCUCCAAAAGUUAGACGAAACAAGAUAGUACAUUAUGAGUCUUAAUUUUAUCAUUGUGGAAAAAUGUGUACUAACUCCUGAUUUUGUUAAUUUUAUAACAUAGGUUGAAUUUUAGAGUGGGGUUUUUAUAAGUAAUGGAGGAUAAAAUGGGUGGGAGAAAAUGGCACACAGCACCUGAAGAAAGAUGGGGCAGUGACCUCUAGAACUCAUGCAUUGCCAUUGGAAAGCCUGUGUUGGGCAUCGAUGUCAGAUCCUGAAGAAUCACCUGGAAAAAAUCCCAUCCUAGAGGCAAGGAGGCUACACCAAACCAUACACUACAGUACUUUGUCACAUGGUUGUCCAUUAUCAUGUAUUAGAGUCUAAAUGAUUACUUGAAUAAAGAAAAAAAACCACUUAACUCUUACAUAUGAAAUGUGUUUUGAUUUUUAAUUUUUGGAUUAAGAAACUCAGAUUGCCAUAAUAACCUUUUAUUUCUUCCCGUGUAUAUUAUUACAAAUUAUAUAUACUUUCAAACAUAGUUUUUUUUUUUUUUAAUUGAGACAGAGUCUCACUUUGUCACCCAGGCUGGAGUACAGUGGUGCAAUCUCGGCUCACUGCAACCUCUGCCUCCUGGGUUCAAGUGAUUCUCCUGCCCCAGUCCUCUGAGUAGCUGGGACUACAGGCGCACACCACCACACCCGGCUAAUUUUUGUAUUUUUAGUAGAGAUGGGGUUUCACCAUGUUGGCCAGGCUGGUCUUGAACUCCUGACCUCAAGUGAUCCACCCGCCUCGGCCUCCCAAAGUGCUGGGAUUACAGGCAUGAGCCACUGCGCCCAGCCUUCAAACAUAGUUUUAAUGUCAGUACAUCUUUAAUGACUUGAAGUUUUAAAACAUUUUAAGCCUUUAAGGUGAAAGCCAUUUAAUUAAUUUGCUCUAGAAAUAAGCACAAAAAAUUAUAGUUAAUUUGAAUACAUGUAUGUAAUGCAUGUCAAAAUAACUUGUUAAUAGCUAUGUGCAACUGUGUUGCAUACAUUGAUCACUAAUGGCAUUUAAAAAUGAUCUGCCUAAAUCUGAGGAUCUGUUUAUUAUAAAUCAGUAGUACUAAAAUAUACCACCCUGUUUUUAUGUUGUGGGUGUUUUUCUUGAUUGAUUGAUCCUGAUAAAUUAAACAGUACCUUCAAGUAUGGACUUUUAACUCCUCCAGUUAAUGCAUCAUAUGUUUACUGGCUAAUAUUAGAUUGAACAUUUUUCUCUCUAUGUCAGUAUCUCCAUAUGCACAUUGGUUGCCGCAUAUAUACAUCUGAGUUUGAAAAGUUCUUCUGAGAUUACCUAAAAGUAACACCACAGAUUCCUUCCAUUGUAAAUACUUUAUUUUAUUUUAUUAUUAUUUUUUAGAGACAUGGUCUCACUUUUGCCCAAGCUGGAGUACAGUGAUGCAAUCAUAGCUCACUGCAGCCUCAAAUUCCUAGGCUCAAGGGAUCUUCCUUAGGCUGGAUGCUGUGGCUCACACCUGUAAUCACAACACUUUAGGAGGCCAAGGCAGGAGGAUCACUUGAGGUCAAGAGUUCAAGACCAACCUGGUCAAUAUAAUAAGAACCUGUCUUUAUGACUUCUUUUUUUUUUUUAAUUAUCCAGGCAUGGUGGUACACACCAGUAGUCCCAGCUACUUGGGAAGCUUAGGCGGGAGGGUUACUUGAACCCAGGAGGUCAAGGCUUCAGUAAGCAGUGAUUGUGGUACUACAUUCCUGUCUGGGUGACAGAGUGAGACCCUGUCUCAACAACAAAAAAGGAUCUUUCCACCUCAGCCUCUCUGGUAGCUAGGACUACAGGCACACAGCACUAUGCCCAGCUAAUAAAAAAUAAUAAUUUUUUAUAGAGGUGGGGUCCGCUAUAUUUUCCAGGCUAGUCCCAAUCUCAUAGCUUCAAGCAGUCGUCCAGCCUUGACCUCUCAAAAUGCUGGGAUUACAGGUGUAAGCCACCGUGCCCUGCCCAUGAUAAAUAUUUUAAUUUUGCCUGAUAAGUCAUAAAAAGUUUAUUCAACACCUUAAAUAGAUUUCUCAAUUUUUUAAAAAUAUUAAACCUUUGAAAUCGAAAGUAAUUUUUGGAUUUCACCCCUUUAUUGCAAGGUUUUUGAUGUCUGUGGGAAAAACCCCUGAAUUGCUUGUGAAACUCUGGAUAUGUAAUUUUUUUUCUUUUUCUGAACAGAGUAAAAUCUUGGAUGGGCCAUGAUCCAAAAAUCAUGGUUUUGAAAGUAGACCGUACUAUAAGCCAUAAUCACAAAUCUGAGGUAAUAGUUGUGAAAGUGUUUAAAACAUCCUGAAAACAAUGUUGAAAAAAAAAAUCUAUGAUAAAAACUAUAAAAUCUCUGCAUAUGUUAUACUGUAUUGAACUUGAAACUUUGAAGGAAUUAGAGUAGAUAAGACAUUAAUGGUAGAAGAGAAACCACAGGGGUGAAUUAUAUCCUACAAAAGAGAAAUCUUCAUGAUUUAACCUUUUUUUUCUGAGUGACUUUUAUUUUGCCUUAUUAACAGAAACCUGAGAAAGUAUGUUGCUUUGUAUUAAAUGGUUGAGACCAUUAUUUGAUAUAAAAGCUGAAAAUUUAAUUUUUGUAUUUUGGAGAAUUCUGUGGUUCCAAGUAAUUGAAAGAAUGACUAAAGCUGUAUGUCAUAGACCCUGCUAAAAUGAAAUAACUUGUUGGGAACAUUCCAUGCAGAUUUCCAAAAUGUAUUUUACCUUAUUAUUAGAGAAAGAAAAUAAACUUUUAAAAUAAUCUGAUAACUAGCAUUCAUAUAUUUAAUAAGUAUUUUGGUUACAGAAGGGAAGGUGAUACUGUACAUUGUAACUGCUGAGACUUUUUUUUAACCAAUGUCUUUGGUAGAUAGCGAGGCACAAUUAUUUUCUCUUAGGGAGGAUUUUGAAUACCUAUUGCAGGCUGGGCAUGGUGGCUCACGCCUGUAAUCCCAACCCUUUGGGAGGCCGAGGUGGGUGGAUCACUUGAGGUCAGGAGUUUGAGACCAGCCUGGCCAACAUGGUGAAACGCCGUCUCUACUAAAAAUACAAAAAUUAGCCAGGCAUAGGGUGGCACACGACUGUAAUCCCAGCUACUAGGGAGGCUGAGGCAGGAGAAUUGCUUGAGCCCGGGAGGCGGAGCUUGCAGUGAGUUGAGAUUGCGCCACUACACUUCAGCCUGGGCGACAGAGCGAGACUCCGUUUCAAAAACAAACAAACAAAAACAAAACAAAAACACCUACUGCAGACCAUGUUCUUUUUACUUUAUUUUAUUUUAUUAUUUUUUUGAGAUGGAGUCUGGCUCUGUUGCCCAAGCUGCUCACUGCAACCUCCGCCUCCCGGGUUCAAGCGAUUCUCCUGCCUCAGCCUUCCAAGUAGCUGGGACUACAGAUGUGCACUACUACGCCCAGCUUAUUUUUGUAUUUUUGGUCGAGAUGGGGUUUUGCCAUGUUGGCCAGGCUGAUCUCAAACUCCUGACCUUAGGUGAUCUUCCCGCCUUGGCCUCCUAAAGUGCUGGGAUUACAGGCGUGAGCCACCGCUGCUGGCUCUUUUUACUUUAGAUUGUAUCUGCCUGAUUUGACAAUGCCAAAUUUUUUAUGUAAUCACCAUUUGGUUUGGGACUGAGAGCUCUUUCAUUUUCUACCAGUCAAACCACUAUUAGAGUCUUCAUGUUACUUCCCCAAUUUGCUAGCAAGGUAGAAUCAGCAUGGAUAGCUUAUUUUCCUUAUUGGAAUUCUGUUUUGGAAGAGGCAGGUCUUAUAGCAGGGCAGACUAAUUAAUGUGCUGAACUCAUUCCCUCCUGCUUAAGUGAAUAAAAACUUUUAUUUGACUAUGGAUUAUAAAGAUUGCCUUUAAGGAGCCUUGUUUAUUUUGGGGAAGGAGAAUGGAUAUUUUGUAGGAGAAAAAGACUUUAUAUAGUAAAUGAAAAGUCUAUGGGCUGGGUGUAGUGGCUCAUACCUUUAAUCCCAACACUUUGGGAUGCCAAGGUAGGAGUAUUGCUUGAGCUCAGGAGAUCGAGACCAGGGAGACUGCAUCUCUAUUUUUAAUUAAAAAGGAAAGAAAAAGAAAGAAAGUUCUAUGACUAAUCACCUUUACUCUAAAAAAAUUUUGCCCAAAUGUGUAAUGAAAGAGAUCAUAUUUAAAUAUCAGCAAUAUUAAUUUGCAUAGCUCAUAAGAAGUCUUGACUCAUUUAGAAAAAGGUUGCUACAGUUUAAUAGUUUUUUAUUGUCAAUAUAGACAAUAUAACUUUAUAACAAUUUUAUGUGAAGAAUAAUGAUUAAAUGGCAUGACUGAAAUGCACAAGGUACAGGUACAAUCCUUAGGGAGUUAUCUUAAAUUUCUUUUUUUUUUUUUUUUUGAGAUGGAGUCUUGCUCUGUCGCCCAGGCUGGAGUGCAGUGGCAUGACUCCCUGCACCCUCUGCCUGCUGGGUUCAAGUGAUUCUCCUUCCUCAGCCUCUCCAUUAGCUGGGAUUACAGGUGCCUUCCACCACACCUGGCUAAUUUUUUUGUAUAGUAUAGACGGGGUUUCACCAUGUUGGUCAGGCUGGUCUCAAACUCCUGACCUCGUGAUCUGCCUGCCUCGGCCUCCCAAAGUGCUGGGAUUGCAGGUGUGAGCCACUGCACCUGGCGGGAAUUAUCUUAAAUUUCUAAAAUUGAAUACCCCAGUCAGCUACAAUUAAUCAAUCACUAAUGUAAAUAUUAAAGCCUAUUCUUAUUUUCCUUGAAAUGAUCUUAAAUGUUGGAAAAGUUUAAUUUUGUAGUCAGAGUUAGUGAAAUUGAAAUUUUUUUAUCACCUGCCCCUAUAAAAUUAGAGAAAUAUAAGAUUGGAAAAAAAUUUGAUAUUUAAGAAAGUGGCAUAUUUGAACCAGGUGUGUUGGCUUACACCUGUAGUCCCAUUAGUUUGGGAGGCUUAGGCAGGAGAAUCACUUGAGGUCAGGAGUUUGAGACCAGCCUGGCCAACAUGGUGAAACCCUGUCUCUACUGCAAAUACAGAAAUUAGCCGGGCAUGGUGGUGGGCACCUGUAAUCCCAGCUACUUGGGAGGCUGAGGCAGGAGAAUCGGUUGAACCUGAGAGAGGGAUGUUGCAGUGAGCCGAGAUUGUGCUACUAUUCUCCAGCCUGGGCAAUAGAGUGAGACUCAGUCUCAAUUAAAAAAAAAAAAAAAAAAUGCGGCCGGGUCCAGUGGCUCACGUCUGUAAUCCCAGCACUUUGGGAGGCCAAGGCAGGCAGAUCACUUGAGGUCAGGAGUUGAAGACCGGCCUGACCCACAUGGAGAAACCCCAUCUCUACUAAAAAUACAAAAUUAGCCGGGUGUGGUGGCCCAGGUCUGUAAUCCCAUCUACUCGGGAGGCUGAGGCAGGAGAAUCGCUUGAACCCGGGAGGCAGGGGUUGCGGUGAGCCGAGAUCGCACCAUCGCACUCCAGCCUGGGUGCAAGAGCGAAACUCUGUCUCAAAAAAAAAAAGGAAGUGGCAUAUUUGGUAAAUUGAUAAAUUACCACUGUCAAAUUAUAUUGGUGAGUCUAUAUCUAUUGUUGUCCCCAGAUGUUGCCUUUGCAAGAAUUAGUGUAAAAUUGGAAAAAAUACUCAAUGUUGAAAGCUGUCAUUGUUGAGAUCUUUAUGAAAUUAUUGUGCCCAUGUCCAAGUUUGAAUUAGAGAUACACAGCACACAAUCAUUUCUGUUACCACUUUUGGAAUAUCUAGCAUUAGCCUUGAUAGUUUUGUGUGGUGUGUUUUGAGUAUAUCUGAACUGUUAGUUAUAUUUGGUUAAUUUAUUAAAAGAUGUGUGUUAAACCUUAAUAUUUAUGCAGUGUUUAAGUAUUUGGAAUAUAUUUGAAAUAAAUUAUCCAGUGUUUUAGAUAAAUGGUUAUUUAAUUGCUUAAAGUGAUUCUCUAAAAAAUAAAACAUUAAUGAAA